AGGAGGGUAUUGGCCAGGUCAAAGGAGAGGGUGGAGGAAAAGAGCCACGAAAUAACCGGGAGACAAGCUUUCGGAGGCUUUUGACUGACUGGAUGUGGGAAUGUUGUGGAAGACUUCUGGCCUGCCAUUUCCUGAGAACGGGACUGCUGAGAGAGGAGCUGGGAGGAGCACUGCAAAUUUCACUUUGGACACGUGAGUCAGAGAGUGGCAGCAUGGAGAGGUGGGGCCUUUAAGAGGUGAUUGGAUCAUGAAGGCUCUAUUCCCACUAAUGAAUGGAUUCAUCAUGGGAGAACUGGCGGCUUUAUAAGAGAGGAAGAGAGACCUGCGCUAGCACCUUAGCACGCUCAGUCCCCCUGCCAUGUCAUGCCCUGAACCCCUCAGGACUCUGCAGAGAGUUCCUACCAUCAAGAGGGCUCUCACCAAAUGCAGCCCCUCAACUUUGGACUUCUCAGCCUCCAGAGCUGUAAGAAAUAAAUUCCCUUUCCUUAUAAAUUACCCAGUUUCAGAUAUUCCUUGUUUUUAAUUUUUAAUUUUUUUUUUUUUUUGAGACAGAGUCUCACUCUGUCGCCUAGGCUGGAGUGCAGUGGCGCGAUCUCAGCUCACUGCAACCACCGCCCCCCCGGGUUCAAGCGAUUCUCCUGCCUCAGCCUCUGGGGUAGCUGGGAUUACAGGCACCUGCCACCACGCCUGGCUAAUUUUUAUAUUUUUAGUAGGGAUGGGGUUUCACCAUCUUGGUCAGGUUGGUCUUCAACUCCUGACCUCAUGACCCACCCGCCUCAGCCUCCCAAAGUGCUGAGAUUACAAGCGUGAGCCACUGCACCCGACCCCAGUUUCAGAUAUUCUGUCAUAAGCAAUAGAAACAGACUAAGUAUCUUUGACAUGGAGUGGAUACUGGAAGCCAUGUGACUUCUGUGGGAUCAUCUCGAAAGAAAGUGUAAAAUGAGAAGACACAAGGGCCCAGGAAAGAGCCCUAGGGAACUCCGCAUUUGUACAGCAAGUGGUGGGUAAAGAGAGAAAAGGGAGAAGCCUGCUAGGAUGCUGAGGAGGAGCAGCCAGAGGAGGGGGAACCCCAGAGAGCGUGCUGGCGUGGGAGUCAAGAGAAGUGUGUCAGAAGAAGGGAGCGGUUGACAAUGUCAGAAGCUGCCAAGAGGCACAAUAAGAUUGAGGGAACAAGUGAGUGUGGUUGUUUCUUUAUGGGCCAGAAUUUUAAAUACCAGGAUGAAGGGCACCUAACAAAUAGCAAAUACACAAACUAACUUUUGUACCUACCAGACUUCAGACUAAAAUCGGUACAAAGAAUACUCGCCAGGGUAAGGAGAAGCCCAGGAAAUUACAAGAGAUAUCUAGUUUCUGAAAUGAAUUACAAUGAUCAUCUGAACAAAUAGUGUGAAAAAAUAUACACCUGAAAAAAUGUGUGAAAAUGGCCAACAAAACAUUGAAAAUCAGGGUUACUGGGGAAGACUUUUACUGCCAGUUAUUAAAAUUUACUAUCAGCUGUAUUGACUGGAACAGCUGCCAGAAUAGGUAAUUCAACAGCCAGGAUGGGAAGCCCUGAUACAUAAGUUUGGUGGGGACUGUAGGUAGCCCCUCUGGCUACCUUCUUUCUAGUUGAAUAGGUUACAUAUCUAACUCCCUUGCAAUUAGGUUCACCUACUCAGGUGCCCUUGAGUUAGACUUGAAAGGCAGAAGACAGCAGAGGCCAUUUUACUGCUGCUUCUGAUGGAGAUGCGAGGCUUCCAUAGGAAAGAGGGGUCCACUGGUAUAAAGAGCCCGACAACCAUGUUCUCCAGAUGUUCAGUCCCUCUUGGCCACCCCACACCAAAUGACAGUCCGCGAGACUCUGCCCAUGGAGACUCCACCUGCUGGUCCUCUAGGUGGAGUAACUGAUAACAAAAAUCUCUAGCUUACUCCUAAGUGUUUAUUCUGAAGGCAGUAUGUACAGCAAGACCAGACUUUUGGCCCAGCUAGCGGUGACUACUGCAAUGUCAAAAGAGCACAUAAACAGACUUAAAAAGCAAAUGACAAACUGGGAAAAUUGCUGUAACAUAGGUAACAAAGGGCUGAUAUUCUAUAAAGAGUUCUUGCAAAUGAAUAAGACAAAGAUGAAUCCAAGUGGGCAAAAGAUAUGCUGUAGGCAAUCUGCAAAAGUGAUGCAUAAAAACAGGUUCAACAUUACUAGCAAUUAGUGGAAUAAAACUUAAAACAACAAUGCAAAACCAUCGUUCUAUCAUAUUAACAAAGAUGACAAAAAAUGGUGUGACAGUGCAGGGUGUGGAGAAAAGUUGGUGUCAAAGCUGUGCCAUCUUUCUGUGUAUCUUUCAUAUCAAACAAACGCCUUCAACAAUGAGCACACCUUUCGACACGAGUUCCCAGACUUUAUCCUAAAAAAAAAAAAAAUGACGUGCACACAGAUUUAGCUACAAGUAAUUUUGCAAAAGUGAAAAGUUGAAAACAACCCAAAUGUACAAAAAUAGGGGAGAUAAUUAUGGUACAUUUGUAUAAUAGUAUGCCACUUGGUCAUUAAAAAUGCCAUAGAAGUAUAUUUUUCAUAAACUUAUUUCUAGCUGCUGGUUUUACAGGUGGUUUUUGCUUUUUUAUUUUAUCAUUUAUAUUUUCCUGUAAUUAUUGCAUAUUUUUUAAUAAUUUUUUAAAACCGGCAAUUAUAUGGUGAAAAGGAGAGAAGGGCAUUAGUAAAUUCUGAAGCAACUGAAAUUAAAUUGUAAUUGCUCAUUAAUAAAUAAACAUCAUUACAUACUAACAUUUACCUUAAAUAAACUAGAUUUCAUUUUUCUACUAUGGGAGGAAAGACCUAAAAUACAAAUUGACUCGAAUUAUAGAAAAUAAAGUUACAAUUCAGGAAUAUCUGUCUUUGGACUGUGAAAUUUGUACCUGUUAUGUAUGUGUGUGUGUGUGUGCCUGUGUGUGUGUGCGUGUGUAUAAAAAAUAUUUGGAAAGAUAUCCACUAGUUUAAAAGUGGUUCCUUUCAGCAGGGUGGGAUGAGAGGGGGACAGGAGACAAAUUUUUAUUUACACAACUCUGUAUGACUUGUUAUAACAAGCACGAAAAAUCGAAGGUCACUUAAGUAAAAAUGGUUAUAAUUAUGAAAAUACUUAGAAAUAUGUAAAGUCUCUAUGGUAUGAUUAGAAAUCAUAAUGCAAAAUCUGUAUACUGUGCUUAUACCUAUGUUCAUAUAUUUCCAUGUGAGAGAAGCCCGAAGGGGAAUACUCUGCGGUGAAAGUAGCUUUUCAAGUUCAUUCAUUGGUUCAUUUAUUCCACAAAUGUGUGCUGAGCUGCUACCAUGGGCCAGCCAACUGUUGCAGCCACCGGGAUAUAGCAAUCAAAAAUCAAAUGUGCCUCCACUCAGGGAACUUAAAUUCUAGUAGUGGGAGACAGACAAUACAUGGUAAACCCGGCGAGUAUUUCAGGAAGUGGUGAGCGUCCUGGGAAAAGUGGAGCAGGCCAAGGGAGACUAGCAGUGCUCUGGGUCAGGGGCAGGUUUAAACAGGUUGGUCAGGAAAGGCCUCACUGAGGUGACAUGGGAGGAAAGAUUUGAAAGAGCUGAAGGGUUCAGUCCUGGAAAUGCCUGGAAGGGGUGUUUUACAAAUAGACAACAGCCGGUGCAGAGGCCAAUGCAGCUAACAGAGGAAGGGGAGAGCAGGUCAGACAGCUAGGCAGGCCAGUGGGUUGUCCGGCUCUGCAGCCAUUGUAAGGACUUUGGCGUUUUAUUUCAAGUAAACUGAGGAGCCGCUGUGCAGUUUGGAGCACAGAAACGACAGGAUCCCUGUGGCUGCUGUACGGAAACCCAGCGACUGGGAGGGUAGGGAGGGCAGGGAGACCUAGGUGUUCAGGUGAGGGAUGAAGGGGGGUGUGGACAUGUUGAGGUGUUGCAUCCUAGACACAGAUUGAAGGUAGGGUCAACAGGAUUUCUAGUCAGAUUGUGUAGAGGGGGUGAGAGAGUGAAGCUGGCUCUUCUGGUUCUGGCCUGAGUAAAUGGAGCCGCCAUUAAUGCCCAUGGGAAAGACAGGUGGGCGGAGAAGGUUUGAAGGUGGGGGAAGAAAGGGUCUUAUUUUCUUCUUCCUUGCAAUAAUAUAUCCCAAGCAAUAUAAUUAAGCAAUAUGUAUUUUUCCCUUUAAGGAAAUUCCAAAAAUUAUAUCGUUCCAAAUAAAAAAAUCAUCUCCAGAGUCCUGACGCAGCAACCAUUACAUUCCCAGUAAUGGAAAUGUUAAGUCAGUCCGUGCUCUGGAGAAAUCCCACGACAGAACACAGGCCAGGAGACCGGGCCUAGAUUCCGGUUUUCGAACCGUGGGGGCAAACACGGAGGCUGCAAAUCCAUCCCCAGUCCGGCAAGAUUCUCGAACAUGUCGGGAGAGGGCUGCAUAGGAACUUCAAAAACGAGUAGCGGCUCCCCUGGAUUCAGCGUGAGGGGGAAACCGCGGGGCAGGUUCGAAACUCAGGAGUCCGACGUCUGAAGGAGCGGGAGGCUGCUUCCGAGGAGCCCGGGGCACGACGGGAAGGGCCGCGCCGGCCAGGCAGCCCUCCUCCCGGCAGCCUCGGGCAGGCCGUUCACGCGCCGGCGACGGCGGGCCCGGCCGCAGGUACCAACAGCACCUGUCAGAGGGCAGCGCGGGCGCACCCUGCAAGGGCCCUGCCUCGUCAAGAGAGGCAGCGAGAAACAGCAGCGAUGAACGAAACAAAACCUUCCUCCACCACGGCUACACAGAGCUCGCGUCCGAGGAAGCGGGAACACACAGGCCCCGGUGCUUUCCGAAAGGCUUCUCGCCAGGACCCGCGACCAGCGUGGGGCGGAGGGGGGGGGUCACCCUUUUUGAGAAACCAGGUCAAGCAGGCCGUCGCUGGGCGACCUUUGGGCGGAGGGAGAGGGCAGGGCUGCACCGCACAGGUUCCGCCCCUACUUCAGCGUCCUCGCCCCUCCCAAGCUCCGCCCAGCACCCCAAGGGCCAACCCCCCCGCGACGCAUGCGUGCUUCUUCCCGCGCGGCUCCACCUGCCGCGCGCUUCCGCUGCUGGCCAGUCUCUUCUGCCCCUCCCCCUCCUGUUAACACAGAAAUCUGCCUCCUGGGCCAUGCCGCUUCUAAGGCCUGUUUCUUCUCAUGAGCCCCAGCACAAGACAGAUGGGCCAGUUCUCACAGUGGAUAACUUCCCCUGCCUGAGCAAGAGAUGGGAUAGUAUCUGGGAUCUGUCCAUCACCAGACUCUGAGCUUAAUAAGGCAGCUGAAUGAAGGGAGGUAACGGACCCCUGAGAGGGGCACUGAAGUCUGCAGUGGGGGGGGAGGGGCCUGGACACACCCCUUCCCCCCCAGACUCCUCCCCGUCAGGGUCAGCUCAGCCAUGGACUUUGGACCUGGAUAAGAAGAGAGAAGCUGCACUUUGGUGGAUCUGAUUUGGGAUUCUCAGUUUUGAAAAUGGAGUGCUGAAUGGGGAUUUGAUGAUCUCCUGGAGAGCAACUGAGACAAGAGAAGAAAGGUGCAUGGCUGCCUCCUAAUCCCAUAGUCCAGAGGAGGCAUCCCUAGGACUGCGGGCAAGGGAGCCGGGCAAGCCCAGGGCAGCCUUGAACCGUCCCCUGGCCUGCCCUCCCCGGUGGGGGCCAGGAUGCUGAAGAAGCAGUCUGCAGGGCUUGUGCUGUGGGGCGCUAUCCUCUUUGUGGCCUGGAAUGCCCUGCUGCUCCUCUUCUUCUGGACGCGCCCAGCACCUGGCAGGCCACCCUCAGUCAGCGCUCUCGAUGGCGACCCCGCCAGCCUCACCCGGGAAGUGAUUCGCCUGGCCCAAGACGCCGAGGUGGAGCUGGAGCGGCAGCGUGGGCUGCUGCAGCAGAUCGGGGAUGCCCUGUCGAGCCAGCGGGGGAGGGUGCCCACCGCGGCCCCUCCCGCCCAGCCGCGUGUGCCUGUGACCCCCGCGCCGGCGGUGAUUCCCAUCCUGGUCAUCGCCUGUGACCGCAGCACUGUUCGGCGCUGCCUGGACAAGCUGCUGCAUUAUCGGCCCUCGGCUGAGCUCUUCCCCAUCAUCGUUAGCCAGGACUGCGGGCACGAGGAGACGGCCCAGGCCAUCGCCUCCUACGGCAGCGCGGUCACGCACAUCCGGCAGCCCGACCUGAGCAGCAUUGCGGUGCCGCCGGACCACCGCAAGUUCCAGGGCUACUACAAGAUCGCGCGCCACUACCGCUGGGCGCUGGGCCAGGUCUUCCGGCAGUUUCGCUUCCCCGCGGCCGUGGUGGUGGAGGAUGACCUGGAGGUGGCCCCGGACUUCUUCGAGUACUUUCGGGCCACCUAUCCGCUGCUGAAGGCCGACCCCUCCCUGUGGUGCGUCUCGGCCUGGAAUGACAACGGCAAGGAGCAGAUGGUGGACGCCAGCAGGCCUGAGCUGCUCUACCGCACCGACUUUUUCCCUGGCCUGGGCUGGCUGCUGUUGGCCGAGCUCUGGGCUGAGCUGGAGCCCAAGUGGCCAAAGGCCUUCUGGGACGACUGGAUGCGGCGGCCGGAGCAGCGGCAGGGGCGGGCCUGCAUACGCCCUGAGAUCUCAAGAACGAUGACCUUUGGCCGCAAGGGUGUGAGCCACGGGCAGUUCUUUGACCAGCACCUCAAGUUUAUCAAGCUGAACCAGCAGUUUGUGCACUUCACCCAGCUGGACCUGUCUUACCUGCAGCGGGAGGCCUAUGACCGAGAUUUCCUCGCCCGCGUCUACGGUGCUCCCCAGCUGCAGGUGGAGAAAGUGAGGACCAAUGACCGGAAGGAGCUGGGGGAGGUGCGGGUGCAGUAUACGGGCAGGGACAGCUUCAAGGCUUUCGCCAAGGCUCUGGGUGUCAUGGAUGACCUUAAGUCGGGGGUUCCGAGAGCUGGCUACCGGGGUAUUGUCACCUUCCAGUUCCGGGGCCGCCGUGUCCACCUGGCGCCCCCACUGACGUGGGAGGGCUAUGAUCCUAGCUGGAAUUAGCACCUGCCUGUCCUUCCUGGGCCCCUCCUUGCCACAUCAUGAGCUGAGGUGGGACCACAGUCCCCAGGCUGCAUCGGCCUGCCUGUGUUUCCCUCUUAGGUGCAUUUAUCUUUUUGAUUUUUCCGAGUGGCAUUUAAGUGCACAAAUGAUAACAAGAGGAUUAUUCUCCCGUUCUCAAGGGAGUCAGAUCAGGGGAACUAUUCUAGGGUAUGUUGCGGGGUAUUAAGCAGGAAACCACUGUGUGGUGGGGGGCACUGGGCUUGUUGGGGCCAGAAAUGUCCACGUCCUGAGCUUUCUCCUGGAGCAUGUGCAGAGAGUUUGGCAACGUUCGCUCUCUUGACCAGACCCCUUCUCCCUGACCUGGCUCUUCCAGCCAGGGCACGAGCCCUCCUUCUAUACCUGCUCCCCUUCCCCCAGUGGGGACUGAGUUAUGGGAGAAGGGGACAUAUUUGUGGCCAAAAUGAUACUAACCAAAGGGGCUUCCUUGUCAGGGCCUGGUGGAGUUGGUGGGUCAUCGGGGCUCACUGCCUCCUGCCCUUCUCUCCUGUCUGACCCCCACUUAGCCCUUCUCUCCUUGCAGCCUAGCAGUUUAUAGUUCUGAGAUGGAAAGUUGAAGGGGGCAAGCAAGACCUCUCCUCAGCCCAUGCCCAGCUGUCAGGAGAGAGGUGCAGGGAGGAAGGCCUUGUGCUGGGACAACCUCUCUCUUGCCUUACCUCAGAGAGGGACUAUGCCCUGACCCCUCCUUUCUGAAAAUCAGUGCCCUCCCUGUUGCUCUAGGAGGCUCCUGCUGGCUUGGUAGAAGACAGAAUUCGAUCUGCCUGUCCCUUUUUCCCCUGGGGUUUGACACACAGGCUCCUCUCAGCAUGAGGUGGAGCAGUGACCAGGUGGAGCAGUGACCAGGACGCCUCUGGCCCAGUGCUGCCCAGCCUCCCCGCCCGCUCCCAGGCGCCCCAUGUCCUCACAGGCCAGGACGCCAUGGCAGGAUGGAGAGGACUUGGUGGAUUUUUGUUUCUUGCCUGACCUCAGUUUCAUGAAAGAAAGUGGAAGCUACAGAAUUAUUUUCUAAAAUAAAGGCUGAAUUGUCUGAAAAAUAUUUAUGUGUGUGUGUCCUGGAAAAGGAGGUGGCAGGCAGGGAAAGAAAGGAAAAGGGAGAAUGAAGAGUUAAGGAGAGGGCUAGACGGGUGGGAGGAAGCAAAGUUGAGGAAAGAAAGCAGAUGAGUGGGAGGGAAGAGCCAGGGACAGCCCAGGGGAUGGGGGCCAGGUGGGAAAGGAAGUCCAGGCCACAAGGUGGAGAGGAGCCCCGGACUGUGCUCCUGCUGAUCGUCCUGUAGAGCCAGGAGGCCGCAGCAGGAAAGCUGGUGAGUGUCUCCUGCUUCUGCCUCCUGCUGGCUGGGCAGGCCUGGUCUGGGGAAGAACCAGGUCCUCUGAUCAGGGUGGUCCCUGAGUGGUGCUUUGUGCCCGGUGCCCUCUGCUGGCCCAGGCAGUGCUUAUUGAGUGCCCUUUAUGACGUGCCGGGGAGCCUCAGGGUACACAGCUGAUACCAGGGUUGGCCUCACAGUGGCGCUUGGACUCCCAAACGCAACCCCAGUGAGAGUGCCUGUUUUGCUAAUACCCAGAACACAGACAGACUGUUACCUCUGCAUAUCACGUGCAACAUUCUGAGAGUUUCUGUUCUCCACUAAUUCAUUUAAAAGAACAAAACGCGGCCGGGCGCAGUGGCUUACACAUGUAAUCCCAGCACUUUGGGAGGCUGAGGCGGACGGAUCACGAAGUCAGGAGUUCGGGACCAUCCUGGCCAACAUGGUGAAACCUAAAAAUACUCUACUAAAAAUACAAAAACUUGCUGGGCAUGGUGGCACACACCUGUAAUCCCAGCUACUCAGGAAGCUGAGGCUGGAGAAUCACUUGAACCCGGGAGGCAGAGGUUGCAGUAAUCCAAGAUCAUACCACUGCACUCCAGCCUGGGCGACAGAGCAAGACUCUGUCUCGGAAAAACAAAACGCUUUUUGUGACUCACGAACUUGAUUUCAUGAGUGGGUUUGAAAACCCUGGGCUAGUCCAGGCGCGGUGGCUCACGCCUGUAAUCCCAGUACUUUGGGAGGCUGAGGCGGGUGGAUCACUUCAGGAGUUUGAGACCAGCCUGGCUAACAUGGUGAAACCCCAUCUCUACUAAAAAUACAAAAAUUAGCUGGGUGUGGUGGCACAUGCCUGUAAUUCCAGCUACUUGGGAGGCUGAGGCAGGAGAAUUGCUUGAACCCGGGACGGGGUGGUUGCAGUGACCUGAGAUCGCACCACUGCACUCCAGCCUGGGCGGUAAGAGCGAAACUGCGUCUCAAAACAAAACAAACCAAAAACCCUGGGCUAGGCAACUUUCUUGGCAGAAACUACUUUGGAGCUCGACACCAGAUGGUGGCAGAGUUGUCUGGGGAGCUGUGUCGAGGGCCGUGGCCUUGGGAGCAGCUCCAACCUCCCAUCUGGGCUCAGAAACCAGUGUCAGACAUUGGUUUUAUUUUAACCUUUGAGAUUUGUGUGGAGCGGGUUUUGCCUUCCCCUGUUGCUUAGAUGGAUUAUUUAGCCAUAUUUUUUGUUAAAUAAGGGGAGGUGGUCAUUAUCCGUGAUUUCAGACGUGGAAUCGGCCCGGCGAUAGCUGCAUUGUGCCCUUUCCGGUGGAGCCAGGAGGAGUUUGGCCGCCACGCUCCAUGCGCAUAGCAUGUCAUGCAGCUAGCCAAGUGCAUUGUUCUGAGUGCUCCAGGAUAAGUACCAACUUACUUAGUGCUCCAGGAUAAGUACCAACUUAGUGCUCCAGGAUAAGUACCAACUUACUUAGUGCUCCAGGAUAAGUACCAACUUACUUAGUGCUCCAGGAUAAGUACCAACUUACUUAGUGCUCCAGGAUAAGUACCAACUUACUUAGUGCUCCAGGAUAAGUACCAACUUACUUAGUGCUCCAGGAUAAGUACCAACUUACUUAGUGCUCCAGGAUAAGUACCAACUUACUUGAUCCUCAGAGCAAGCCUAGGCGGUGGGUACUGUUUUGCUCCUGUUUUACCAGUGAGGAAGCAGGCACACAGAGGUGAAGUUGCCCAAGGUCACACAGAUGGUUGAGGGAGAGCCGGAUUGGAAUGAACUCUGUGCUGUUAGCCACUGUGUGAGGCUGGACUGUUCCAUUCCAGCCUUUACGGCCUCUUCCAGGCCAUUCCCCAGCUGCACUUGGAUUCUCAGGCCAGGCACCGGCGGUCUCCUGUGAGGGUGGAGAGGAAGAGGGGGCUGCGUGGCUCGGGGAGGUCCAGGAGAGAUGGCGGGAGGAGUAGAGUUUGGGGCCUGCGGUGCCAGAGGACCCCCUUACAAGACGAAAGACUGGGUUCUCAGGCUCCUGAAGCAAGGAGCACCUUCAGGGGUCUCCUGGUAUUCACCCAUCAAGGCUUGCUCAGGUGGCAUGCGUGUGUGCGUGGCGGCUGCCCCCGGGCCCGGAAGCGCCUGUGGAUACCAAAGCAAGUGGAAAUGCCAGAUGGAAAAGCCCCGUGUUAGUCAAUGCUGUAGAGUUCAGCCAGCCUCGAGUUUGCAGGUUUACAGAGCUGCCUUGCGCCUGGCUGCUGCUGCUGCUGCAUUCCUGCUUCUGCCUCCAGCUGUGACCACCUCCUGCCACUCCUGCUCUCACUGUGGGUUCCUGCUCACUCUGUCUCCAGGACAGACUGCCUUCCGGGCAGCCUUCCCUCCUCAAGCCUCUUGGCCUUUGCAAUCCUCUUACCUGGGUCACUGGUGGGAUCUCAUUUGUGGAUCAAGUCGCCCCCAGUGGAGACAAAUGUCUGAUGGAGUCUGGCCAAGGCCCUCCUGAGCCUUCACUGGGCCCUGCAUGAGAAGCCUGCCAAGGCUGAGGGGCCAGGGAAACGGAGACGAAGCCCUCAGAGCAGGCCAAGAGGGUGGGAGGUGGGGGGCAUUUAGAGGGUUAGAUACAGAGCACCCCUUUACAAAUACCAGCUACUGGCUUUUCGUAUUACAUGUUCAUUUUAGAUACAACAUACUGCACACGCUCCCUUAACGUGUGUUUACGCGUGGGUGGUGUAUCCUUCCAGACGUCUUCCUCACAUCUAUACAUAAUAUGCAUAGAUAAAACAUUUACCACCAAAACCCAUAGUGUUAUGUACAUAUUUGUCUGGCUGUGUAACUUUAAAUAACAUACAAAUGUAUAGAACAGAAGCUUGCCCUCUUUCUGAAAUAUCUAACGUGGGAUUUCAGGCUUUCUGAUGAGACCUCUGUAGAGGUCAGUGUUUUGCCACCAGAGGUCCUUCAGCCUCCAUCUGUUCUCCCACCUACCCACAUUCUGGCCCCUGGCAAUUCACAGGGAGUUUAGGAAGUAGACACCAGGGCCCUAUUUCCUGGAGACCAGCCUGGUGGCCGAUGUCAUAGAGUGCGGUGGGCCUGGGCCGGCCCUGCUCUGGGCCCGUGACCUGCGUGUCUGACUCGGGUCCAGCUGUUCUUCCUGCCAGAGCCUCUUCCUGUGAGGCGGGGGUAACACAACCUUCUGUGGUGGCUGUGGGAUUAAUCCGUAUGGCUGCAUUGUGAGUAAAGCCUGGUGGAAAUCUCUGUCUCCACUGCUUUCCUUUUCCUGCUGUUCACCUUGGCUCCCUCGACACUUAAUCCCCCUCCACAUGUGUCUGGAGCGGGCAGAGCGGGGGCAGUUGAUAGAAAGGGGGCCGGGUAGUGCCAAGGCUGUUACUUUCCCCCACUGCCUCCCUUGGCUAACUUGAAGUCUGACCCUUUAUACCAGAACUGUAAGACAGUGUGUCAGAAUGGAUUCAGUUGCAGAGCAGGAAGCCUGGAUCCCAGCGCCGGACGGAAAUGAGAGGUCGAUGGUGCAGGCUGGUGUGGGGGUUCCUCCACCGUCAGGGCCCAGGCUCCUUCUCAGGUCUCAGUCUCACUCUUCUUAGCACGAGGUCAGGUCUCAUUCCUUGGCUGCGGGAGCUCCAGCCAGCACACGUUUUAGGAAGAAGGAGGAAGGAAGAAGGUAAAGGGUGGAUGGCAGCUGCCUCCUCCUCUCUUGGAAGCUCACAGAGCGCUGGGUCACAAUUCCCUGGGUAGAACUGGAUCACACAGGCACCCCUGUCAGCAAAAGAGGCUGGAAAAAGUAUUUCUGAAGCUGAAUCAAAUUAAGAUUCCUGUUACUAAGAAGGGAGUGAUUGUAUGGGCGACUACAGGGACCACGGCCAUACACGGUGCCUGGAAGACCAAGCUUGUGACAGUGACGAGGAUUUGGAGAGGGCAGGGUGAUGGGGAGCUUUGGGGGGAGUGCAUUAGGAACCCUGACCUGGAGAGGGGCAGAAUGAAACCUGCGGGCCCCUAACCCUAGUGGGUUGUUUGAGAAACCUGUCCUACUGUGGCAGGGGGCUGAGUCUUCUCAGGGUCAUGCAUGAAAACUGAAAUUCCUGAAGGCCACACACAGCCCCGGAAGUGCUGACUGACAAGGGCACAUGCCAGUGAUGCAGUUUUCUUUUUUGUCUUCACUUUUGUUGUUCCGCCGUCUUCAACACAUGGCUCCCAGCUCACAGCAAAUGCUGCCCUGGUUCAGCUACCAGGAAGCAGGAGAGGGGAAGGGAGGGCAAGCCUCAUUCUUUAUGGAACAAAAGCAGUGGGCAGACAGCCUUCCCUCACGUUCCACUCACUGGAAUGUGGUCUGGCUGCCUUCCCUGCAGGAGGUGGGAUGCACCCUCAGUGCAGCAGCCCUGCCCCAGCCAAAAACGUCUCAGCACAGCUGUAAGAAGAGGAAGAUGGCUAGAGACAGGCAGCCUUCCCUGCAAGGGCAAUGAGGCAAGCCUGCCAAAAGCCUCCUUUGGAAAUACUGUUUGAUUACUUUUCAGAGUUUCUAUUUAGGAAAAGGGCAAAACCUUUCAGGAUCAGGAGUAGGUGAGCGGCGAUCAGGCCUCACUCUUCACCGAGGGCCUUCCCUGAGGAGGGGCCUGCAGGACGCUGGCAGCGGAAUGGGGCUGUGUGGCUGCUAGAUUAGGUCAUGGCAGGGAGACAGCCUCUUCCUGGUUCUUGCUAGAACAGGCACACUUGGGGCCUUGAGCUCCAGGGAGUUCAUGGAAGACAUCUGACUACCCUGAGCCCCUUGCUGGAGGGUUCUGGGGAGUGGCCCACGGCCACCGUCACCCAUGGCCACCGUCACCCACAGGGGCCGUGAGGACAUCCCUGGCCAGCAUCUAACACAACCACAUGGGAUGCCCUAAGCAACUACUGCCCAGCCGAGGGCUGCCUGAAUUUCUGACUCACAAAUGGUGGGCAAUGUGAAACGGGUAUUUUAAGCUGCUGAGUUCUGCGGGAGUUUGCUGAGCAACAGUAGAAACCAGAACUCUCGGAUACUGUGUUCUGUCCUUGAAACGGUGGAAGAUUUUAUGUGACCAGAAUGGAAUGUUUGAACAAAUAUUUUGAGAAUAGAAUUUUAAAACAUUUACUCAUCAGCAUCCAAGGGUGGGGAGCAGUGUCAUCUAGGAGACUGGUUCUAUUAUUUACGUAGAUGUUCUUGAAUUAAAGGAUGGGAAUAUUUUUUCCUUCCAAAACUUUUUUUCAAUUUUAUAUUCUGUUUUUCAAGUUUUUAUUAUGAAAAUAUUCAAACUCACAGGGAAGUUGAAAGACUAAUACAAAGAAGAACCAUACUCUUUCCACUGACAUGAUCCAACGAGGAAUAUUUUGCCACACGGCAAAUAUAUACCGUAUAAUUUUCUGUACCACUUGAUAGAAAGGUAAAGAAUGAAUAUUGUUUUUUAAAUAACUUUUUUCGUAUAUAAGUAAUAUGUGCUUAUCGUGUAACUACCUAAAAACAUUGAAAAAUAAAAGGAAAAUAAAAUUCAUACAUAACC